AACCACCCCUCUUCCACAAAGAAAAACUUUAAAUUUGCUUCUGGUCCAGCAACUCAAUUUUGUGUGACAUAUUGCAAUAUAUAUGCCCUUCAAAUACAGUUGACCCUUGAACAACACAGGUUUGAACUGUGUGGGUCCACUUAUAUAAGGAUUUUCUGCUGCCUCUGCCACCCCUAAGGCAGCAAGAACAACCCCGCCCCCUUCCUCCUCCUCUGCCUAUGCAGCAUGAAAACAGCAAAGCUGAAGACUUUUAUGAACAUCCAUUUCCACUUAAUGAAUAGUGAAUAUAUUUUCUCAUGAUUUUUUUAACAUAUCACCUUAUAAAACUAUAGAAUAUAUAUAACAUACAAAAUAUGUGUUAAUCAACUGUUUGUUAUCAGUAAGGCUUCCGGUCAACCGCAGGCUAUUAAUAGUUAAGUUUGUAGGGAGUCAAAAAUUAUACAUAGGCCGGGCACAGUGGCUCACACCUGUAAUCCCAACACUUUGGGAGGCCAAGGUGGGCGGAUUACUUGAGGUCAGGAGUACAGAAGCAGCCUGGCCAACAUGGUGAAACCCCAUCUCUACAAAAAAUACAAAAAAUUAGCUGGACAUGGUGUCACGCACCUAUAAUCCCAGCUACUCAGGAGGCUGAGGUAUGAGAAUUGCUUGAGCCUGGGAGGCCAAGGUUGCAGUGAGCCAAGAUUAUGCCACUGCACUCCAGCCUGGGUGACAGGGAGAGACUCUGUCUCAAAAAAAAAAAAAGUAUACAUGGAUUUAUAUACUUGAAAAUUGCUAAGAGAGUAGAAAGAAUUCUCCUCAUAGAAAAAUGAGUGGGUGGUCAGCACCCCUAACCCCUACAUUGCUCAAGGAUCGACAUAGUUUUAGGAAUGAAGUUGAUGAGUUUUGCUGAUAUAGCUUGUGGUUGAUUGAUAGAUUUCCUCUGGGUCUUUCUCUGCCUUCUUUUUUAUUUGAAAUAGGCUAAAACAUCAUGUUCUUAGAGCUUGUCAUUUAAAAUUUAGUAUUCAAUACUUAUAUCAUUUGGAAUAUAGCUGUAGUCUUAUAAUUCAGAAGGUAUAGCUUUGCUUGUAAUGUUUUAUAGGCCUACAUAGUGAGCUCUUAAAAUGGCACUGCUUUAAAAAAUUUCUCAUGAGUAUUUUGCUUUUAACAGAGAAAUAACUUGCUCCAGAGACCAGGCUUUCAUUCUUUUCUCUCCUGGUAAAAAUUGACUGACUUUCUGUGAGUUCUACAAUUUUCUGUAUAUAUCUGUCAGGACAAGUGUUGUAUUGUACUUUAUUUUAUUUAUUUAUUUACCUUCUUCUCUCCCCCACAAUGCUUGCUAGGGUUAGGAAACAGUCUUAUUUAAAUCCUAACAAUGCAUGGUAUGUAUUAAUAAUUAGAAGGUCACUUAAUGUUAAAAAUGAUUAUCAAAUAAAUAACAUAUAUCUUUGUGUUGUUUUCACUGUCUCCUGCUAAUUCCAAUUUAGUCCAUUUUUAAUUUUCUGAUGAUUAAAUGAAAUUUAGUGAGUAAACAAAUCAGUAAAAUAUAGUAUCUCUUUCUGCUAAUGUAUUAGAAACUAAGUUUUAGUAAAACUUUGAUCGUGUACCCUAGGUACCUGACUGCAAAUGUUACUCAUCCUUAAGGAUUAAGGUGAUCUAGGUGUGGGUUUAGCAGACCUUUGUAUUGGAAUCUUAUGAUGAUUAUAGUAGUAGCUAACAUUUAUAAAAAGGAAAAUUUCACUAUUUGUUGUUUUUACAUGCUGUUUAAUUUAUCUAAUUUAAUUUUCUAUAACUUUAUAUGUCAUCUAGAUGUUCUUAGCUUCAUUUUAAAGAUGGAGAAUCUGAGGCAUGAAGAAGUUAAGAAACUUGCCUGGGUAUAUAGUUACUAAAUGAUGAAGCCAGUUUUUAAAUCCCAGACAGUCUAAAUCCAGCACUGUGCUCUUAAGCACCAUAUGCAUAUUAAGUAAGUUUUUAGCUUACACAUGAACUUUGUAUUCCAGGAACAGUUAUGUUAGUAAAAUAUUAAAUGGUAGAGAAUUUUUUCAUAAAGCAAGACAGAUAACUGUCUUGCAAGAGUCACCCAUUCACCACGAGAGAGAAAAAUAAAAGAAAUGUGAGUGAGUGAGUUUAGGGCUAAAUACAUGUAAAUACUGAGUUUGUCAGAGGAAUCAGGGAGGGAAGUAAAGUAGAUUUUUUUUCUUGGGUAAGAAAUAAAAGCAUUUAGCUCAUUUGCUUAUAAAAAAUAGUAAGAGGAAAACUCUAGCAAAAUAAAUCUAGAGUCUUGGUUGAGGCCCACUAAUGCGAGAACAUCUGACCUCUUGGUUGGGCUAAAUCUCUAAAACUGAUAGGAAUAACAAAAAUAUACUUAAUUUUGGUCAUAUCCUGGCAGAGGGGAAAGGAGGGCAGGAAGAUAGAUAGCCUCAAAAUCCAGGUACAAGAAAGGAAAGGGGAUAUUCAGAGAAAGAAAAAAACCAUAAAAAGGAAGAAAUACUAGAUGGUGAGGGAAGAGGAGAGAGAUACCGAUCUUUUCUAUCAUGCAAUUAUUGGCUAAAUUUGCUUCUUCCAGAUUCCCCCUCAGCUACACGAAACUUCUAAUAAAGGGGGUUCUUAUCUUCUAAAGCAACCCCUAGUCCUAUGCAUGUCACCAAACUAAUAAGUGUCUUUUUUUCAUUCCCUGUUUUAUCCUGUCUUUGCUGCUUAUUCUGAAGCACAACCACAACAAAUCAACCACUGUUUGGAGAGUUAUUGCAAAGUGUGAUGCUUUGCAGGUGUAGAGGAAAAUGAAAAAUAGCUUCUUCCCCAGAGGGUUUUACAAUCUAGUUAGGAAUUUUAAAUGUAACUUUAUUAAAAGAUAAUUAACAAUAUCCUACAAUAUUAUGAGUUGUGUGGUAUAUACAAUUCCACACUUACCUAUUAGCUCAACCUCUUAUUUUUUAUUUUAUUUAUUUAUUUUUUUGAGACAGAGUCUUUUACUGUUGCACAGGCUAGAGUACAGUGUUGCAAUCUUGGCUCACUGUAACCUCCGCCUCCCAGGUUCAAGUGAUUCUCCUGCCUCAGCCUCCCUAGUAGCUGGGACUACAGGUGUGUGCCACCAUCCCCAGCUAAUUUUUUAUUUUUAGUAGAGAUGGGGUUUUGUCAUGUUGGCCAGGCUGGUCUCAAACUCCUGACCUCAGGCGAUCCCUCCACCUCAGCCUCCGAAAGUGCUGGGAUUACAGGCGUGAGCCACCGUGCCCAGCCAGCUCAAGCUCUUUAACCAGGUCUUCUCAGCAGGGCACUGUGUCUCCUGCUUUACAGAAAAAUUAGGUAGAAAGACAAAUAUCUUCACCUCCUCUCAUCUUCUUCCCUUCAUUCUUAGAUAAAAGUAUCUCUUCUCAGAAAAGGCUCAUUCUUUGUCUUGUUUUUUCUAUUUUAGCCCUUCACAUCUCUAACGCUGGAGCUCUGCUCCAUGUCCUUACGUGUUAGUAUAAAUAACUCUGUUGGUUCCUUCCCUCAACCCUGUAAAUCUAUUACUCUUACAUUUAAAUAAAAACACCACUGUCAGCUUUGCAGACACUCUCUUCACCCCCGUCUGGUUAAACCCUUUCCAUCUUCAAUCACAUUCCUUAAAAGACUGCCUUACCUCCCAGCCUCACUUCAGUGCAUUGCAGUUAUGCUUCUGUUCCCAUGACUCCACUGAAACUUCUCUGGUAAAGAUUCCUUAAUACUGGCCAAAUCAGAUGGACCAUUUUUAGUCAUUGUCUUUUGAUAUCUUUGCAGUCUAACAUUAUGUCUCCUUUCCUGAACCUAUGACUAGCUUUCUGACAGUUUUUAUUCUGUCUUCUCUGCUGGAUAACUUUGGCCCUAUUCCUUUCUCACUCCAAGUCAUCAAUUCUCACAACUCCAGUUAUCAGAUAUGUCCUAAUAAAGCUCCGAAGUGUAAUCUCUAAUUCAGGCCUCUAUCUUAAGCCCAAGACCUAGUUAUACUUUUGUUAUAAUGACCUCAAACUCAGCAGAUCCAAAACCACACAUCUUUCUGCUCCCUCAUUCCCCACACUGUUUUUUUUCCUUUGUUCUCUAUCAGUGCAUGUUAUUGAACCAUUUAUUCAGUCAUCCAAAUAGAAAAACAGGGAUCUUCCUGUACUUUUUAUCCUCUUAUGUAAUCAAUGACCAUAUUCCAUCAAUUCUGUCUUGAGUAUCAUCUAUUAAAAUUAUCCCUUUAUGGCUGGGCACUGUGGCUCACACCUGUAGUCCCAGCACUUUGGGAGGCCAAGGUGGGUGGAUCACGAGGUCAGGAGAUCGAGACCAUCCUGGCUAAUAUGGUGAAACCCUGUCUCUACUAAAUAUACAGAAAAUUAGCCAGGCGUCAUGGCGGGCACCUUUAGUCCCAGCUACUCAGGAGGCUGAGGUGGGAGAAUGGCGUGAACCCGGGAGGCAGAGCUUGCAGUGAGCCAAGAUCAAGCCACUGCAUUCCAGCCUGGGCAACAGAGUGAGACUCCGUCUCAAAAAAAAAAAAUUAUUUAUUUCUAAUUUCUGGUAGAUAAAUUUCUGGCAGUAAUUUUUUUUUUAAAUUCUCAGCACUUUGAAAAUUUUUUAUAUACAGUAGUACUCAAAUAUCUGGAUGAAUAGGAGUUUUGAAAAAGAGAUUUGACUGUAACAGAAAAGAGAGAAGAUGAUUCUUAAUCAUAGAAACAGCUGAGACUGGGUCUCACAAGCUUUUUCCCUGAAAUUAGAUUUCGAUUUGAGAAGAAAGAAAUGGCCAGGGUACAUAAUAUACAAAUUAGUAAUGCACUGCACAAGUGGGAGGUGGUGGGAAAAAAAGCCCUAUAUACUUUGAUGUGCAAGAGGACCUUUUUUGUUAUAUGCUAAUUAGAAAGCACUUUGUUACAGAACUUUUUGGCAGCCCUUCUAACCUUAGGAACCUCUAAGCAAUCAUUUAAUUUGGGUCCAUUUAUUGUAAAGAAGAGUAUAGUUGACACCUGAAUUAUAAAACUACAGCCUUACAUUUGUCUGGUGAUUCAAGUAUAACGACAUACAAUCUGCUUUCAAGCCUCUCACCAGUCAAUAGCAAGAAUUUGAAUUCCUUCCUAGCCUGUAAUGUUUCAAACACAUUAUAUAUUCCCCAACCCACCUCACUCCUGUUAAUCUUUCAAGUAACUCCUAUACUUUGAUGAAUCUGUACCAGGUAUUAAUCAAAAGAGAAGUGCUUUCCUGAGUCUUACUUGUAGAAACACUCUUUUGAUGGCUUCUACUUUUCUGUAAAGGCCUUUUUGUUUUGUUUUUGUUUUUGUUUUUUUGAGACGGAGUCUGGCUGUGUCGCCCAGGCUGGAGUGCAGUGGCACGGAUUUCGGCUCACUGCAAGCUCCGCCUCCCGAGUUCAUGCCAUUCUCCUGCCUCAGCCUCCCUAGUAGCUGGGACUACAGGCGCCCGCCACAACGCGCGGCUAAUUUUUUUUAUUUUUUAGUAGAGAUGGGGUUUCACCGUGUUAGCCAGGAUGGUCUCCAUCUGACCUCGUGAUCCCCCUGCCUCACCCGCCCAAAGUGCUGGGAUUACAGGUGUGAGCCGCUGUGCCUGGCCUGUGAAGGCCUUUUGUAAGUAUUAAUCUGGAUCAUUUUGCCUCAUUCCAAUGUCUUUUAUCAGCUUUUGCUGUUAGUUUAUCCUUAGAUCAAUCUCUUCAUGUUCAUAACUCCUCACAUUUAGUUUGGUUUAGGUUUCAUCCCUUCACAGCAGUUUUUGGUGCAUGUGUGUUUAUAGCUGUUAUGUUGUUAAUGUUUUAUUUUGAGUUGGUUUAAAUUUAUAAAGUGCAAAUGUAAAGCUUAAAAGCAACAAAAAGAGAUAAAUUGUUUGUUAUUACAGGUUUCUUUCUUUUUUUUUUUUUUUUAAUGGAGUCUCACUCUGUCGCCCAGGCUGGAGUGCAGUGGCGCGAUCUCAGCUCCCUGCAAGCUCUGCCUCCCAGGUUCACACCAUUCUCCUGCCUCAGCCUCCCCAGUAGCUGGGACUAUAGGCACCCGCCACCAUGCCCAGCCAAUUUUUUUUUUAUUUUUAGUAGAGACGGGGUUUCACCAUGUUAGCCAGGGUGGUCUCAAUCUCCUGACCUCAUGAUCCGCCUGCCUCAGCCUCCCAAAGUGCUGGGAUUACAGGCUUGAGCCACCGCACCCAGCCCCUAUUACAGGUUUCUUAAUGCUAGUACUGCAGUUAAUAUUUUCAAACAACUUGGAAACUUAGUUAAGAAAAAUGAUUCUCAUUGUUAAUUAUAUUCAUUAACUUAGCAAAAUGUUUAUAAUGAAUCUUAAUAUCUUAAUAUUUUGGUUUUAAAAAUCAAUGAAAAGUGAUAAUUCCUUUAGUUUUGUUACAAUUCAUGUGGAUUUCAUUGUAUUUUAAAUAAAACAAAAGGAAAAAGGAAAUAUGACUUGCUACUUUGUAUACACAUUGUUUAUUUUAUUUCCUACUAGGAAAAAUACUUACUUUGGGGACUUUAAGCUCUAAGCAAUAGUACCUUAUUGUUAACCAGUUUAAAGAAGAUCCGAAAAGUAGUGCCAAAGGGCAACCAAAUAAUUUUAGUGAAUAUUUGCAUAGUGCAUUAAUUCAUGCUUUUCUGCUGCCUAGGGUUUAGCCACUCCUCAAAGCAGCCCAGGUUUUUUGUCUGUAUCCUGCCUGCUUUUGCCUGUGUGUUGUGUGCUCACUGUCCUUCAGUUUGUCCCCUUUUAUAAAAUAGAACACUUUCUUUAGUUCAGAGAGCAAAAGGGCAGGAGAAGAGCUAUCUUAAGUUUUAUUUUUGCCAACAUAGAAGUAGUUUGUGUGGUAGGCCAUCUGGACUGAGAGGAUUUCCUCGGAAUGUAAAGUAUGUUGUGAGAUCUAGAGAGCUGAGAUUUGCUUUGAAACUAUCUGGGAAGGUGGUAUUCCUACGCAGACAGAACUGGUUUAUAUUGCUUACAACAUCGGUGGUGGGAACGGAAGACAGCUUGCCUUGUCUCGCUUCAGUGUGGGGUUCCUCUACCCUUAAGAAUUUCUGACCAGGUAAACUAUCUCUCCAUUCCUGUGAGUUCAGACCUGUCUCACAAACUUGUGACAAAAGAAGUCUGAGGACUUGGGAAUGAAUCUAGAUUCCUUGCUCCCUCCAUUAGCCCCCUUCUCCCUGUAAAUAUAUGUGUCAGUAAUGUGAUAAACAUUUGCCUACACACUUGUAUAAAGUACUUAAAACUACUUACUUUAUAAACAAAUAUAUUCCUGUUGAGAGGACAGGGUGGGUUUUGCUCAGCUUGUUCUUGUUCUCUGUGAAAAAAGAUGGUCAUGUAUAUAAAACAGCAGCUUUUAAUGGAAAAUAAUUUAAAAGUGCCUGUCUUAAUAAUACAUCAGAAAUUGUAUAAUUAAGCUUGACUUUUACUUUUGUGAACUCUAACCAAAAAACAUCAUCAAAAACAAUUAUCUAGGCCGGGCACUGUGGCUCAUGCCUUGUAAUCCCAACACUUUGGGAGGCCAAGGCGGGUGGAUCACUGGAGGCCAGGAGUUCAAGGCCAGCCUGGCCAACGUGGCGAAACCCCAUCUCUACUAAAAAUACAAAAAUUAGCGGGUCAGGCAUGGUGGCUCAUGCCUGUAAUCCCAGCACUUUGGGAGGCUGAGGUGGGUGUAUCACCUGAGGUCAGCAGUUUGAGACAAGCCUGGCCAACAUGGUGAGAUCCCGUCUCUAUUAAAAGUACAGAAAUUAGCCGGGUGUGCUUGCAGGUGCUUGUAAUCCCAGCUACCCGGGAGGCUAAUGCAGGAGAAUCGCUUGAACCCGGGAGGCAGAGGUUGCAGUGAGCCGAGAUCGCACCACCGCACUCAGUCUGGGUGACAAGAGCGAAACUCCAUCUCAAAAAAAAAAAAAAAGUAGCAGAGCAUGGUGGCGUGCACCUGUAAUCCCAGCUACUCAGGAGGCUAAGGCGCGAGAAUUACUUGAGCAGCCUGGGAGGCAGAGGUUGCAGUGAGCUGAGAUCAUGCCACCGUACUCCAGCCUGGGCAACAGAGCCAGACUGUGUCUCAAAACAAACAAAACAAAAACACUAUACACAGUGUGUGGUAUUGUUACUAGUUUCUCAUGGUCUUCACUCAACGUUAGCUUCUCUAAUCUAACCUAAUCUUCUGCCAUUACCAUUCUAACCUAUAAGGGCUGCACAGUAUCUCAGCAUAAGUGCUUUAGGAAGGGGAGAUCAGAGACUAUUUCAAAUUUUUUAACAACUUAUUUGUUCUUGGGAUGAUAUUAUAUCUCAUAUCAUGUAACUUUUUGAAAUGAAGGACUGUUUUUUUCCUUAGGUUUGUAGAUAAUUAAUCUUAGAGUCAUACUAUUAGGCCUCAAAACUGUCAUAAAGACCAUCUAGUAUAGUUGUUUUUAUGCCACAAAACCCCAGGGUUCUUAGAAAUACAACUUCAUUUUUGUUUUGGAACUUAAUUCACAAAAAAUGGAUUCAUUGUUCUCCAAAGAAUAAAGUGAAUAAAUCAGUUAUGUAGACCAGUUAUCAUAUCCCCCAUCUACUUUUACAGAAGAGAAACAUCACUGAACUUCCCUCCCCCUCCCUAAAAAGUUACAAUACAUGUUUUAAUCACGUAGAUGUUCCAUUAUGUGUGAGUGUCUCACUGUCCUAUCCUCUGUCAUACAACCAUCAGAAGUAACUAUUGUCAUAAAUUUUGUGUAUAUCAUUCCCUUGGUUUUUCAGUAGUUUUAUUCUAAACAUUGUAUUAUUUACUUUUGUAUGUUUUUGAACUUUAUAUAAAUUUCACCUGACUUGCUCUUUACAUUCAUCAUGUUCCUGAGAUUCAAAAUGAUGUUGCACAUCGCCAUAGUUUACUUUUACUAUUCUGAUAUUCUGUUGGUUGUUAAUAUCACAAUUUACCCGUUUUACAAUUGAUAGAUAUUUAGGUUGUUUCCAAUUUGUUUUUAUGAUGAACUAUGCUGCUGUGAAUAUUCUUGGACAUGUCUUUUGAUGUAUGUAUGUCUGCAGGAGUUUCUCUAGAACAGAGACUGGGAGACUGCCUGGGAGGCCACCUGUUUUAUAAAUGAAGUUUUAUUAAAUGAAGUUUUAUUGGAACAUAGCCACACCCAUUCAUAUACAUAUUUCUAGCUGUUUUUGUGUUACAAAGGCACAUCUGAGUAGUUUGCUCCACAGACUGUGUGGUCUGCAAAGCCUAAAAUAUUUAACUAUUUUCCCCUUUACAGAAAAGUUUGUUGACUCCUACUUUAGGUUAGGGUAACACAGUGGAAUUGCUGGGUCAUAGGAUGUGUGUGUCUUCAGUUUUACUAGAUAUUGCCAAGGUUUUUUUUCCCCCUAAAGUCAUUGAAACAGGUCACUUUCUACCAGUGAUGUUGGAGAGCUUGUAUCCCUCCAUAUCUUUGGGAACACUGUAUGUUGUCACACUUUACGUUUUUGGCCAGUCUGGUACGCAUAAGAUAGUAUUUUGGAUGGUUUCAAUUUUCCUUUCCAAGAUUAUUAAUGAGGUGCUUGAGUCUCAUUUUAUGUUUGUUGACCAUUUAUGUUUCCUUUUCUAUGAGGUGUUUAGAAAGACUGGCAAAACCUUUGACUAACUAUAGAAUUGUUUGUAGUCUCAACCUCCCUGGUCUCAGGUCAUCCUCCCACCUCAGCCUCCUAAGUAGCUGGGACUACAGGUGUGCCACCAUGUCUGGCUAAUUUUUGUAUUUUUUGUAGAGACAGGGAUGCCAUGUUGCCCAGGCUGGUCUCGAACUCCUGAACUCAAGCAGUCCUCCUCCCUCGGCCUCCUAAAGUGCUGGGAUUGUGGGCAUGAGCUACCAUGCCCAGUCUGGAUACUAAUUUUUAUCAUUUAUUAUGUGUUACAGCUAUCUUUCCCAUGUGUAUGGAUUACUUUCUCUCUUUAUUAUGUCUUUUGGAGACCAAACAUCUGAAUUCCAUUGUAGUUAAGUAUCAGUAUUUUAUGGUUUUUUUGGUGUCUUUUUUGGACCUUCCUGUUUGUAGGAUAUGAAGACAUUUGCAGUUAUUUUCUAAAGAUUUUAUGAUUUUGCCUUUAAUUCUUUAAUCUUCUUGGAUUUUAUUUUUGUGUGUGGUGGAGAUAUGGGCUUUAAUAUAUGGUUCACCCUUGAAUAACAUGGGGGUUUGGGGUGCCAACUCCCUCCCUCUCCCGCUCAGUCAAAAAUCCACGUAUACUUUUGCUUCCCCAAAAACCUGACUACUGAUAGCCUACUAUUGACCAGAAGCUUUACUGGUAACAAGUUGAUUCACAUAUUUUUGUGUAUUACAUAUAUUAUAUGCUGUACUCUUAUAAUAAAGUAAGCUAGAGUAAAGAAAAUGUUAUUAAGAAAGUCAUAAGGAAAAUUCAUUUACUAUUCAUUAAAUCAAAAUGGAUCGUCAUAAGACCUUCCUCUUCGUCAUCUCAACUACUCAACAUGAGUUGAGUAGGUUGAGGAGGAAGAGGAGAGGUUGGCUUGCAUUUUCCUGUUAAGUACUUAAGUAUGAAUAAGUUUUAAAAAGUGAUUACUUAUUGGUAGCAUAUAAGUUCAGAGUCAGGAAUGAUGGUUAUGCCAAAAAACAACCAGUUGUCCAUGUGGGUGUCUGAAAUAGUGACACCUUUGUUUUCUGAUAGUUCAGUAUACACUUUAUUUCAUGCACAAAAUUAUUUUUUAAAUACUGUAUAAAAUUACCUUCGGGACAUGUAUGUAAGAUGUAAGUGGAACAUAAAUGAAUUUUGUAGUUAGACUUGGAUCCCCUCCACAAGAUAUCUCAUUAUGUAUAUGCAGAUAUUCCAAAAUCUGAAAAAUUUGAGACCUGAAACACUUCUGGUACCAAGCAAUUCAGAUAAGGGAUACUCAACCUGUAAUAUGUUUUUAAAAUAGAAGAGGUCCUCAUUUUAGAGACUUCUCAUAUAAACAGUUCAAAAAGCUUAGUUAUUCAAUGUACCAUAAUAUAGGAAAUUAGAUUGGAAAGGGAGCAUUGCUAUGGAUAGGCAUAGCUAAUCCCAACUGCAAAGAGGUAAGGGGAAAAGUAGAAAGAAAGAUUAGAAAACCAAAAAUGUGGUCUGGUGCAGUGGCUCAUGCCUGUAAUUCCAGCACUUUGGGAGGCUGAGAGGGGAGGAUUGCUUGAGGAUGGGAAUUCAAGACCAGCUUGGGCAAUAUUGUGAGACCCAUCUCUACAAAAAAGAAAAUUAAAAAUGUAAUUUUGUUUUUAUUUUUUUAUUUUUUAUUUUUUUGGCAAUAGGGUCUUACUCUUUUGCCCAGGCUGGAGUGCAAGGGUGCAGUUAUAGCUCACUGCAGCCUUGAACUGGGCUCAGACAAUUCUACUGCCUCAGCCCCUGAAUUACAAGCAUGUGCCACCACACCUGGCUAACUUUUAAAAAAUUGUUAUUUAUUUGUUUUAAAGACAGGGUCUUGCUCUGUCACGCAGACUUGAGUGCAGUGGCACAGUCAUGCCUUACUGCAGCCGUGACCUCUUAGGCUCAAGUGAUCCUCCUGCCUCAGGACUGGGACUAUAGGUGUGUGCUGCCACCCCCUGGCUAAUUUUUUUUGUAGAGACAGGGUCACCCUAGGUUGCCCAGGCUGGUCUUGAACUCCUCGGCUCACGCAAUCAUCCUGCCUCAACGUCUCAAAAGUGCUGAAUUAUAGGCCUGAGCCAUGGUUCUCAAUUAUUUAAUUAGAAGUAUAAUAGCCUCUAGGGCAUCAUUUCACCACAGUGCUUGCAGCGUAGUAAUUAAUAUUCUAAAUGAAGACUGAGUCACCAAGAAGUGGUUACAUUAUGAUGGUGUGCCCCCACUAAGAAAACAAGACAGUAAGUAUUCUGUUUUAGAAAGAUAUAAAAUCGGUAAAAUCCAAAGGUACUAGAAUGUGUAGGCAUGUCUUAUUCUGAUAUGAUACUGGAUUGCCAACUUUUGGAUAUUUAUAAUGAAACACAAUAUACUUACCUUUGCAAAGGUGACACAUUUCUCAACAGUUCAGAAAAAAAUUAACUGUGAUUCAGUGUAAUAAAAGCAUAAUGAAUAGCUAUCAUUGUAUUCUUUAAACUGUAAUAUUUCAAACUUUAUAAAGUUUACGAAGUCACAUGUAGAUUUCCUUGUAUUUCUAAAAAGAGACUGACUCAUGCCGGUAAAUAGAUCAGACUGAUAGUGAGAGGUUUCUGGAUCUCCGUUUUCUCUUCAUUCUUUACUUUUUUUCUUAAUGAGUUCAAAAAUGCUUGAGAAUUCAUUUGUAUUUCAUAUUUUAACCUUCAAAGCUGGAAACUAUUUUGAGAAGGGGCAACAAUUUUUAAAAACCAGGGGGCAAUUAGAAAAAAUGUUUAAAGGGAGGGGAUUACCAUUUUUAGCUUAUACUCCUACUCUAUAAUAAAGGCGGCGGGGGGUGGGGUGUAAGGAAAAUGAUCUAAUCUACUUGAUCAAGAAAAGGGAAUGUUAAUAGCCCUCAGAAAAUAUAUUCAUUUACUGAACAGUUAUAUCCCUUAGUUUAUUGUGAAUGAGAAUGGGGGCAUCUUAGAGAUUGGGAGGGAAAAAAAAUAAGAGCAAAGUUUUCAAAAUGGAAAGAACAAGAGCAAUGCAUAAUAUAGUCAUCAGAGGAAGGAACUCUGACUCGUUUGCUGUGUGGCCAUGGGUAACUCACCUGAUGUCUCAGAGUCUUAGUUUACUUAUUUAUAAAAUGAUGAGAGGGGUUGUUGGACUUCAAGAUAGUGUCUGUUCUUGUUUUAGUAAUCUAUGAUAGAAAUUUAAGUUAUUUGCAUUCUCCUUUGCUAUGUUCCUUAUAACACUGGAACACUGUAACUGGAGGAAACUUGUUUUAAGAAGUUAAGCUUCAGAAGCAAUGCAUUUUACCUUAAAGGGCAUAAAUUAAUACACAUUUUUAUUGUGAAAUUCGAAUAAUACAGGAAUACAUACACUAAAAAGCAAAAAUUUAUUUUUAUUUCCUCUUUUCUAAUCUUACCUUCCUAGCCAGAGGUAACCCAGUUACCAGUUUGAUGUGUGUACUUCACAACUUCUUUCUGUGUACAUUAUAUAUACAUAUGUGUGUGUGUAUAUGUGUGUUUUUUGUGUUAAUUUUUUAAAAGUGUGUUUUGGUGUGUGUCUAUCAAUUAUUCAGUACAUAUUGUUUUGCAGUUUGCUUAUCCACUUAAGUCAUCUUGUAGAUUUUUCAAAUUUUUAGCUUAUGCUCCUACUCUGUUAUUUUAAAUUAUUCCAUGAUAUUCUAUGGUAUGGACAUAUUACAGCUUAUUUAACCUCAUCCUUAGACUUCAGGUCAUUUCUAAUUUUGUGGCAAUAAUAAACAGUGCAAUAAAGAACAUCACUAUAGGAUAGCAACUUACUGAAAGCAUCCUGUAUUGCCAUGCCAUGCAUUAUUUCAUCUAAUCAUCCCAAGCCUGAUGUAAGUACCAGUUCACAUGAGUAAAUUACACGUGAAGAAAGCAGUCACAGAGUUGGUAAAUAGCAAACAGAUGGCCGGGCGUGGUGGCUCACACCUGUAAUCCCAGCACUUUGGGAGGCCAAGGCAGGCAGAUAGAUCCCUUGAGGUCAGGAGUUUGAGACCAGCCUGACCAACAUGGCAAAACUCCAUAUCUACAAAAAAAUAAAAGUUAGCUGGGUGUGGUGGCAUGCGCCUCUGUAAUCUCCCAGCUACUCCGAGCCUCAGCUAAUAGAAUCUGAGGCAGGAGAAUCUCUUGAACCCAUGAGGCGGAGGUUGCAGUGAGAUUGCACCACUGCACUCCAGCCUGGUCGACAGAGUGAGUCUCAAAGAAAAAAAAAAAGCAAACAGAUAGAUGUAUUUAGUCAGUGUAAUACCAGAGUUAAUGCACUAUUCUACCACAGCUUUUAUUGAAUUCUCAAAGAAAUUCAUGCCCCUGAAAGGGUUAAGAGCCAGGAUUUUAGACAGGAAGGAAUUAGAGCUGUGAGGAACUCUGGUGAUAACUACUAUGCUCUGUUACAUUGCCAUUGCUUGUUGCCUUGGCUAUAGUGACCCUGUAAUUGAUCAUCCAAGUCAGGGAACUUGAGAGUGAAAGAGGGGGCAUUAUGAUAAUAUUUAUACUGAGAUAGGAGACAUACUUGUUCUGGAGAAACUGAGAUACUUGAACAUGUUAACCCUAACAUAGGCCAUCAUCACCUUUCACAUGGGUUACUGCAACAGCCUCCUGUCUGUUCUUGUGUUUACUCUUAUCCUGUUCCAAUCUAUUUUCACACAGCGACCAAAAUGAUCUUCCUGAAACAAAAAACGGAUUAAAUCACUCAGUAGUUUAAGCCCCUUGCGUGGCUUUGUGAAAGGAUGUAUUUGUUUGGUCCUCAUGUGAUUAUUGUUAGAAUGCAGCAUAGAAUAAAAUAAAAGGCACAUAAGGUGAGAGUCAAAAGACUUGUCUUUGAGUCUGAGAUACCUAGAUUAGUUUGGUGACCUUGAGCAAGUUAUUUAGUUUGAGCUAUUUCCUCCAGUGUAAAAUAUAGAUUGUGUGUGUAUGUGUGUGUGUCGGGGGGGGGAAGCUGAGGUAAUAAAUAUGAAAGGCACAAUAUAAAUGCAGGCAAUUGUUAACUUUGUAUAUGUUAUGCCCUUUGAAAAAUUGUUCUUGUGUCUCACAGUGUCUAUCAGGGUUUGGUAGGAAUUUUACAAGCUGAACCACCUUUCUUGUCACUAUCCAAGUUUCACACAACUUAAACACCUUAGUCAUUUUUUAAAAAAUCAAAGUUUGUAAAAGUUUGCUGAAGGUAAGUUACCAAGCUGGUACUAAAACCUAGCACCCUAACCUUGGCAUUAUAGCCUGAUGAUCUAGUAGUUCAGCUGCCUUCCCAGAAUAAUUAAGCAGGUUAUAUGUUUACAAAAAUCAUAUAAGCAUUUUAUCUGUGGUCAUAAUAUAAAGAUAUAGCUCAUCUUUCAUGAAUUGAGAACAUUUUAGAAAAAUAUAUCCAUAUAGUUUACUGACUUAAUCGCGGCCUUUGGUUUACAAAUAAUGGCUUGCAAAAAGUGAAUUUAUUACGUUACAUAAUUAGCUGGGAGGAAUAUUGGAGCAGCUCUCAGAAUUGAAGGGCCAAGGCUUCAGAGAGUAUAACUGGAACACAAGGUAGUUAGAACCACCUUUAUUUUUGACAGUCCUAGGGUGACAUCCUGGUAGCUGGAGAACCAAGGUGGAUGGGCUAUAACUCUACCUCUGGGAAAUUCAAGAGGGCUUCAUUUGGCCUAUCCUGUAUCUCAUGACUACUACUCCUGUGGUAGUAUUAGACUGAGCCAUAUUAACUAACUCACUUCCUUCCUCCCUCCCUCUCUCCUUUCCUCCCUCCCUUCCUUCCCUUUUUUCUCUUUUCUUUUCUUUCCUUUUCUUUUCUCUUCUCUUCUCGUCUCGUCUCGUCUCUUCUUUUUUUCUCUUUUCUUUUUUCUUUUCUUUCUGAUAGGGUCUUCCUCUGUCACCCAGGUUUAAGUGCAGUGGUGUAAUUAAAACUCACUGAAUCCUUGAAUUAAACCCAUCUUUGACUGGGUUUAAGUGAGCCUCCCAUUUCACUUUUCUGAGUAGCUGGGACUACAAACACGUGCCACCAUGCCCAGCUAAUUUUUUCCAUUUUUGUAGACAUGGGUUCUCACUACGUUGCCCAGGCUGGUCUCGAACUCCUGGGAUCAAGCGAUCCGCCCACCUUGGCCUCCCUAAGUGCUAGGAUUACAGUCGUGACCUGCCUUGUCCAGCUGAAAUUUCUAGUAGUAAUAUUUAUACAACUGAAAAGGUCAUUUUAUAUGGUUCAGUCUCAUAGUAUGGGGCGCAGAGGGUAAAGUGAAGCAUCAUAGAUUGACAGCUCUACUAGGACCAAGAAAUAUGGUGGAGUUUCACAAAAGACAAGAGUGGCUAUUCUUCCUGUGAGAAGAAGGAGAAUAGGAAAGAAUUUUGGGUAGAAAGAAUAGUGACCAUAGUCUAACAUACUUACAAAGAAUAUAGAUCAGCUAGAAUUCAGCUAGACCACCGUGGAAGUGAAAAAUACUUAAAAUAUAAAAAUUUCUAAGGCGAGAGACUGAAUUGUUCUUAUCAUUCCUUAAGCAUCUCAGAGUUGGACACAUGUGCCUUUAAGUAACAAAUGUGCUCAAAGUUUUCAAAUUGUAACUUUUGUACUUUGUACAUAUCCUAGGCACACCCUCCUUAAAACAAUCCUAUUUAAAGGUGAAGAAAUUAAUGCUCAAAGAACUUGCCUAAGAUUAUGUAACUAGUUAAUAUGGAACCAGAAUUUGAAGUCUAGAUUAAAGAUGAAACCCAACUUUUCCUUCAAUAUCUACGUCUCAAAGAUAAGACUGUCAGUGAAAUACCAGUAAAGACAGAAGAGAGUACAUGUGUAUGCAUGGGAGGUCUGGUGGUGUAUAUCAUCUUAAAUAUGAAAUAUGAAUAUUGUUUACUGUUCCAUAAUGUAAUGGUGAUAGCUUUGGUUUUUUAAAUGUUGUGGUGGUGGUUUUAAACUUUGAAUUAAAUUAAGUUCCAUAGCAUAUUAUCUCAGUGUGAGAAAAAAACAGUACAUUCUGCCUUAUUGUCUGAAUGACUGAAACAGUCAUUUAAAUGAUCUCAGUGUGGUCCAAACAGCUCUUACAUUAGAAUCUAAAACUUGCCCUCAGUGUAAGCCAACGGUGUUUUUAACAGUUAGUUAUUUCCCUGAAUUUUCCUGCUUAUACUGAAUGAACCAAUAGCAAUUAAUGUUUUUUUUGUUUUUUGUUUUUUGUUUUUGUUUUUUGUUUUUUUUUUUUUUUUGAGACGGGGUCUUGCUCUGUUGCCAGGCUGGAGUGCAGUGGCGUGAUCUCGGCUCACUGCAACCUUUGCCUCCUGGGUUCAAGCAAUUCUCCUGCCUCAGCCUCCCAAGUAGCUGGGACUACAGGCACACGCCACCAAGCCCGGCUAAUUUUUUGUAUUUUAAUAGAGACUGGAUUUCACCUUGUUGGCCAGGAUGGUCUCGAUCUCCUGACCUCAUGAUCUGCCCUCCUCAGCCUCCCAAAGUGCUGGGAUUACAGGCAUGAGCCACCGCGCCCAGCCAGCAAUUGAUGUUUCUAUAUGUUUGGAUUCUUAUUGACCCAACAAAUACAGUAGUAUAGUCUAAAGUUACAUAACUUUGCAAGUCCUUUGUAAUUGCUGUGGUAUAGCUAAGCCUUAUUUGAAUAGUCUUUCUCUUGUUGCUGUUACAUACCUAAGGCAAAUAUUAAGUAUUUACUUCAUAAAAACCUUUUUUUAAGAGAGGUUGUGGUGUUAGGUGGAGAGAAGGAGCAGCAAAAGGUCUUUUGUUAAUUACAUAGCAAUACCGAGUUCUGUGGGGUGUGGGAGAGUAUGAUAGUAAAAAGUAAAGUAGUAAAGAUGCUUCCUCAUCAUUGUUGGUUAAGGUGAUAGACUCCCUAUCUGAUACAUAAAACCAAACAAGUGAUUUAUAUGCCUUUUCUGUUUUCAUAGAGAACUGUGAUAAUAAUGUAAUUAAGAAAGGUUAAAUAGUUUGCUGUCUUGGAAGUUUCCUGAUGUCUACAAGAUGAUGUAUUUAGGGAGCCUUUUCGUGAGAAAACCAAUUAAGAUGAUGUUGUAAAAAUAGGGGAAAUUUGACCGUGGGGACAAUUGUCACCAUUUUAAUGAUUUGUGAAGUUUAUUAACUUAUUUUAAAUUAAGAUAGCUAUAAAAGUCUUUAUAGAAGUUAAUAUGUGUCAACAUGAUGAGAUGUUAUGGAGUUUUUUGUUUUGAAAUUUUCUUUCUUUUUUUUUUUUUUUUUUGAGACAGACUCUUGCUCUGUUGCCCAGACUAGAGUGCAGUGGUGCAAUCUCAGCUCACUGCACCCUCCACCUCCGGGGUUCACAUGAUUCUUGUGCCUCAGCCUCCCAAAUAGCUGGGAUUACAGGAGCGCAUCAUCAUGCCUGGCUAAUUUUUUGUGGUGUUAGUAGAGACGGGGUUUCACCAUGUUGGCCAUGCUGGUCUCCAACUCCUGACCUCAGGUGAUCUGCCUCUCUUGGCCCCUCAAAGUUCUGGAAGUACAGGCACGAGCCACUUCACCUAGCCAGAAUUUUUCUCAUCUUUUAUGAUAGUAUUUCUGCUGCAAGUACUUCUGAUGUUCAAGAUCGCCUGUCAGCUCUUGAGUCACGAGUUCAGCAACAAGAAGAUGAAAUCACUGUGCUAAAGGCGGCUUUGGCUGAUGUUUUGAGGCGUCUUGCAAUCUCUGAAGAUCAUGUGGCCUCAGUGAAAAAAUCAGUCUCAAGUAAAGGCCAACCAAGCCCUCGAGCAGUUAUUCCCAUGUCCUGUAUAACCAAUGGAAGUGGUGCAAACAGAAAACCAAGUCAUACCAGUGCUGUCUCAAUUGCAGGAAAAGAAACUCUUUCAUCUGCUGCUAAAAGUGGUACAGAAAAAAAGAAAGAAAAACCACAAGGACAGAGAGAAAAAAAAGAGGAAUCUCAUUCUAAUGAUCAAAGUCCACAAAUUCGAGCAUCACCUUCUCCCCAGCCCUCUUCACAACCUCUCCAAAUACACAGACAAACUCCAGAAAGCAAGAAUGCUACUCCCACCAAAAGCAUAAAACGACCAUCACCAGCUGAAAAGUCACAUAAUUCUUGGGAAAAUUCAGAUGAUAGCCGUAAUAAAUUGUCGAAAAUACCUUCAACACCCAAAUUAAUACCAAAAGUUACCAAAACUGCAGACAAGCAUAAAGAUGUCAUCAUCAACCAAGCAAAAAUGUCAACUCGCGAAAAAAACAGCCAAGAAGGAGAAUAUAUUAAAAUGUUUAUGCGCGGUCGGCCAAUUACCAUGUUCAUUCCUUCCGAUGUUGACAACUAUGAUGACAUCAGAACGGAACUGCCUCCUGAGAAGCUCAAACUGGAGUGGGCAUAUGGUUAUCGAGGAAAGGACUGUAGAGCUAAUGUUUACCUUCUUCCGACCGGGAAAAUAGUUUAUUUCAUUGCAUCAGUAGUAGUACUAUUUAAUUAUGAGGAGAGAACUCAGCGACACUACCUGGGCCAUACAGACUGUGUGAAAUGCCUUGCUAUACAUCCUGACAAAAUUAGGAUUGCAACUGGACAGAUAGCUGGCGUGGAUAAAGAUGGAAGGCCUCUACAACCCCACGUCAGAGUGUGGGAUUCUGUUACUCUAUCCACACUGCAGAUUAUUGGACUUGGCACUUUUGAGCGUGGAGUAGGAUGCCUGGAUUUUUCAAAAGCAGAUUCAGGUGUUCAUUUAUGUAUUAUUGAUGACUCCAAUGAGCAUAUGCUUACUGUAUGGGACUGGCAGAAGAAAGCAAAAGGAGCAGAAAUAAAGACAACAAAUGAAGUUGUUUUGGCUGUGGAGUUUCACCCAACAGAUGCAAAUACCAUAAUUACAUGCGGUAAAUCUCAUAUUUUCUUCUGGACCUGGAGCGGCAAUUCACUAACAAGAAAACAGGGAAUUUUUGGGAAAUAUGAAAAGCCAAAAUUUGUGCAGUGUUUAGCAUUCUUGGGGAAUGGAGAUGUUCUUACUGGAGACUCAGGUGGAGUCAUGCUUAUAUGGAGCAAAACUACUGUAGAGCCCACACCUGGGAAAGGACCUAAAGGUGUAUAUCAAAUCAGCAAACAAAUCAAAGCUCAUGAUGGCAGUGUGUUCACACUUUGUCAGAUGAGAAAUGGGAUGUUAUUAACUGGAGGAGGGAAAGACAGAAAAAUAAUUCUGUGGGAUCAUGAUCUGAAUCCUGAAAGAGAAAUAGAGGUUCCUGAUCAGUAUGGCACAAUCAGAGCUGUAGCAGAAGGAAAGGCAGAUCAAUUUUUAGUAGGCACAUCACGAAACUUUAUUUUACGAGGAACAUUUAAUGAUGGCUUCCAAAUAGAAGUACAGGGUCAUACAGAUGAGCUUUGGGGUCUUGCCACACAUCCCUUCAAAGAUUUGCUCUUGACAUGUGCUCAGGACAGGCAGGUGUGCCUGUGGAACUCAAUGGAACACAGGCUGGAAUGGACCAGGCUGGUAGAUGAACCAGGACACUGUGCAGAUUUUCAUCCAAGUGGCACAGUGGUGGCCAUAGGAACGCACUCAGGCAGGUGGUUUGUUCUGGAUGCAGAAACCAGAGAUCUAGUUUCUAUCCACACAGACGGGAAUGAACAGCUCUCUGUGAUGCGCUACUCAAUAGAUGGUACCUUCCUGGCUGUAGGAUCUCAUGACAACUUUAUUUACCUCUAUGUAGUCUCUGAAAAUGGAAGAAAAUAUAGCAGAUAUGGAAGGUGCACUGGACAUUCCAGCUACAUCACACACCUUGACUGGUCCCCAGACAACAAGUAUAUAAUGUCUAACUCGGGAGACUAUGAAAUAUUGUACUGGGACAUUCCAAAUGGCUGCAAACUAAUCAGGAAUCGAUCGGAUUGUAAGGACAUUGAUUGGACGACAUAUACCUGUGUGCUAGGAUUUCAAGUAUUUGGUGUCUGGCCAGAAGGAUCUGAUGGGACAGAUAUCAAUGCACUGGUGCGAUCCCACAAUAGAAAGGUGAUAGCUGUUGCCGAUGACUUUUGUAAAGUCCAUCUGUUUCAGUAUCCCUGCUCCAAAGCAAAGGCUCCCAGUCACAAGUACAGUGCCCACAGCAGCCAUGUCACCAAUGUCAGUUUUACUCACAAUGACAGUCACCUGAUAUCAACUGGUGGAAAAGACAUGAGCAUCAUUCAGUGGAAACUUGUGGAAAAGUUAUCUUUGCCUCAGAAUGAGACUGUAGCGGAUACUACUCUAACCAAAGCCCCCGUCUCUUCCACUGAAAGUGUCAUCCAAUCUAAUACUCCCACACCGCCUCCUUCUCAGCCCUUAAAUGAGACAGCUGAAGAGGAAAGUAGAAUAAGCAGUUCUCCCACACUUCUGGAGAACAGCCUGGAACAAACUGUGGAGCCAAGUGAAGACCACAGCGAGGAGGAGAGUGAAGAGGGCAGCGGAGACCUUGGUGAGCCUCUUUAUGAAGAGCCAUGCAACGAGAUAAGCAAGGAGCAGGCCAAAGCCACCCUUCUGGAGGACCAGCAAGACCCUUCGCCCUCGUCCUAACACCCUGGCUUCAGUGCAACUCUUUUCCUUCAGCUGCAUGUGAUUUUGUGAUAAAGUUCAGGUAACAGGAUGGGCAGUGAUGGAGAAUCACUGUUGAUUGAGAUUUUGGUUUCCAUGUGAUUUGUUUUCUUCAAUAGUCUUAUUUUCAGUCUCUCAAAUACAGCCAACUUAAAGUUUUAGUUUGGUGUUUAUUGAAAAUUAACCAAACUUAAUACUAGGAGAAGACUGAAUCAUUAAUGAUGUCUCACAAAUUACUGUGUACCUAAGUGGUGUGAUGUAAAUACUGGAAACAAAAACAGCAGUUGCAUUGAUUUUGAAAACAAACCCCCUUGUUAUCUGAACAUGUUUUCUUCAGGAACAACCAGAGGUAUCACAAACACUGUUACUCAUCUACUGGCUCAGACUGUACUACUUUUUUUUUUUUUUUUCCUGAAAAAGAAACCAGAAAAAAAUGUACUCUUACUGAGAUACCCUCUCACCCCAAAUGUGUAAUGGAAAAUUUUUAAUUAAGAAAAACUUCAGUUUUGCCAAGUGCAAUGGUGUUGCCUUCUUUAAAAAAUGCCGUUUUCUUACACUACCAGUGGAUGUCCAGACAUGCUCUUAGUCUACUAGAGAGGUGCUGCCUUUUCUAAGUCAUAAUGAGGAACAGUCCCUUAAUUUCUUGUGUGCAACUCUGUUUUAUCCUAGAACUAAGAGAGCAUUGGUUUGUUAAAGAGCUUUCAAUGUAUAUUAAAACCUUCAAUACUCAGAAAUGAUGGAUUCCUCCAAGGAGUCCUUUACUAGCCUAAACAUUCUCAAAUGUUUGAGAUUCAAGUGAAUGGAAGGAAAACCACAUGCCUUUAAAACUAAACUGUAAUAAUUACCUGGCUAAUUUCAGCUAAGCCUUCAUCAUAAUUUGUUCCCUCAGUAAUAGGAGAAAUAUAAAUACAGUAAGUUUAGAUUAUUGAAUUGGUGCUUGAAAUUUAUUGGUUUUGUUGUAAUUUUAUACAGAUUAUAUGAGGGAUAAGAUACUCAUCAAAUUGCAAAUUCUUUUUUUUACAGAAGUGUGGGUAACAGUCACAGCAGUUUUUUUUACCAACAGCAUACUUAACAGACUUGCUGUGUAGCAGUUUUUUUCUGGUGGAGUUGCUGUAAGUCUUGUAAGUCUAAUGUGGCUAUCCUACUCUUUUGGGCAAUGCAUGUAUUAUGCAUUGGAAAGGUAUUUUUUUUAAGUUCUGUUGGCUAGCUAUGGUUUUCAGUACAUUUCCUACUUUAAGAGUAAUUACUGACAAAUAUGUAUUUCCUAUAUGUUUAUACUUUGAUUAUAAAAAAGUAUUUUGUUUUGAUUUUUUAACUUGCUGCAUUGUUUUGAUACUUUCUAUUUUUUUGGUCAAAUCAUGUUUAGAAACUUUGGAUGAGUUAAGAAGUCUUAAGUAUGCAGGCGUUUACGUGAUUGUGCCAUUCCAAAGUGCAUCAGAACUGUCAUUCCCUUCUAAUAUCUUCUCAGGAGUAAUACAAAUCAGGUAUUUCAUCAUCAUUUGGUAAUAUGAAAACUCCAGUGAACUCCCAAGGACAUUUACAACAUUUAUAUUCACACGCUGUAUGGAAGGGUGUGGGUGUGUGUGAAGGGGCGAGUGGAGACACUGUGUGUAUCUCUAGAUAAGAAGAUAUGCACCACGUUGAAAAUACUCAGUGUAGAUCUCUAUGUGUAUAGGUAUCUGUAUAUCUUUCCUUUUGUUUACAACUGUUAAAAAACCUCAAAAUAGUUCUCUUCAAAAGAAGAGAGAUUCCAAGCAACCCAUCUUUCUUCAGUAUGUAUGUUCUGUACAUACUUAUCGGAGCGCGCCAGUAAGUAUCAGGCAUAUAUAUCUGUCUGUUAGCAAUGAUUAUUACAUCAUCAGAUCAGCAUGUGCUAUACUCCCUGCAAGAAAUAUACUGACAUGAACAGGCAGUUCUUGGAGAAGAAAGAGCAUUUCUUUAAGUACCUGGGGAAUACAGCUCUCAGUGAUCAGCAGGGAGUUUAUUUGAGGACAUCAGUCACCUUUGGGGUUGCCAUGUACAAUGAGAUUUAUAAUCAUGAUACUCUUCGGUGGUAGUUUCAAAAGACACUACUAAUACGCAGGAAGCGUUCCAGCUAUUUAAUGCUGGCAACUACUGUUUAAUGGUCAGUUAAAUCUGUGAUAAUGGUUGGAAGUGGGUGGGGUUAUGAAAUUGUAGAUGUUUUUAGAAAAACUUGUGAAUGAAAAUGAAUCCAAGUGUUUCAUGUGAAGAUGUUGAGCCAUUGCUAUCAUGCAUUCCUGUCUCAUGGCAGAAAAUUUUGAAGAUUAAAAAAUAAAAUAAUCAAAAUGUUUCCUCUUUCUAA